AAGCACAGCAGCUACCAGCAACGCUUGGACCCGCGCCGGGUGCAGCUCUGCGUCCCCGCGGCCGCCCUGCCUGCUCCGAGGGCUGCGCCAACGAUAACGCGCACCUGUGGGCAGGGGCCAGGUGCCGGCACCCGAAGGAGUGCGGCUCGGCGCACGGCGGCCCCUCCUACCAGGUGAACGGCUCCCAGGCUGGCCUGCCCCUGACUCUGGCUGGGGGGCACACUCCAGGCCUUCUUCACGCCCUUGGCCAUCACAGUCCAGGUGGCACCCGGCCUCUCCAUGACCUUUCACGAAUCCCAUGCCCUCUGAGUGGCAGUGCCUGAGACCUACACCAACACCCUCUGUGGCCUGGGCGGGGACUUCAGCGUGGAUACCCAGGAUGACUUCAGCGGCUCUGAUAGCACAUGGCUCUCUGAUGCCAACAGCUUAAUGGGGGCCCAGCCCCUCUGUGCCCACCAGACAAGGCAGCCCUAUACCAGGCCUUCUGUGGCUUGCUGGGCACCCAAGAUGGGCCCUACAGGGCCUGCAGUAAGGACGUGGAUCCCCAGGUGCAUGUGGAGAACUGCAUCCAUGACCUCUGUGCCACGGGGGGCUCAAGAGAGACUCUGUGUGCCAUACUGGGGAGCUACGCCCAGGAAAGCCAGCAGCGCAGCGUUCCCAUGCAGCCCUGGAGACACCUCUUGGCCUGCAGUAAGUGGGUAUUCCCAGGGAGGGUCUUUCUCAGCCUGACCUCCCCAGCUGGCCCAAUACCACUUCCAGGAUGUCCUCCUAGGUCAACACCACCCAAAGUGACCCACUGCAUGCCUUUCUGGCUAACUGUUCCCGCGAAGAACCUACCUGCUUAAAACUCUGCAAUAACAAUAACAGAUGACACUGAGUGCUAUUGCAUCAGUCAGGAUGGUCUGGGUUAUGCUGAAGUAACGAACUAACCUGAACAUGACCCAGCAUGACCAAGGUUGUUUCUUCAUCACUAUCUUCGUCACCUUUGUCAUCAUCACAGUCACUAUCAUCAUUACCGUCACCAUCACCACCACCACCAGCGUCACCAUCACCACCACCACCAGCCUCACCACCACCACCACCACCAGCAUUACCAUCAUCACCACCACCACCAUCACCACAAGCAUUACCAUCAUCACUACCACCACCAUCAUUGUUACCACAACCACAACCAUCACCACCAUCACCAUCAUCAUUGUUACCACAGCCACAGCCAUCAUCACCACUACCAUCACCACCAUCAUCACCAUCACCACCAUCACCAUCAUCAUCACCACCACCACCACCAUCAACAUCAUCAUCACCAUCAUAACCAUCACCACCAGCAUCACCAUCACCACCAGCAUCAGCAUCACCAUCACUACUAUAAUCACCAUCACCAUUAUCACUACCACCACCAUCAUUGUUACCACAACCACAACUAUUGUCAUCACCACCACCACCACCCUCACCACUAUCAUCACUGUCACCAUCACCGCUAUCAUUACCAUCACCAUCAACACCAUCACAUCACCAACAACAUCACCAGCCCUACCACCAUCAUCAUCAUUACUAUCACCACGACCACCACCACCACCAUUAUCACCACCAUGAUCACGCCACCAGCAUUAUCACCACCGUGACCACGCCGCCACCGUUAAUCACCGCCGUGACCACGCCGCCACCGUUAUCACCGCCGUGACCACGCCGCCACCGUUAUCACCGCCGUGACCACGCCGCCACCGUUAUCACCGCCGUGACCACGCCGCCACCAUUAUGCUACAUCCUGAUGAUGCCUCCACCUCCCCUCCUUUGCCUUUAUGACUUACCCUUGGCCCCCACAACCCUCUCUCCGCUCCCUUGGUCCUAUUCUGGUUGGAAAUGCUCCAGAAUAGUAAUGCUUGCUCAAUUAUUUAACUCCUACCUGUUUUCUUCCAGAGCUGGCCUGUCCUCCCCGCAGCAAUUACGAGCUCUGCGGCUCCUCCUGUCCUAGCUCUUGUGCCGAGCCUGCCCUGCCCGACAGCUGCCUGACACCAUGCCAGGAUGGCUGCCAGUGUGACCCAGGCUUUGUGCUCAGUGGCAUGGACUGCGUGCCCCCAAUCCAGUGCAGCUGCUCCAUGGGGGGCAGGUACCACCACCCGGCUGGGGAGGCCUUCUGGACUGGGGAGCGCUGUGAGCAAUUCUGCCACUGCCAGGCCUCCACCCACGCCGUGUGCUGCUCCCCGUCCUCCUGUGGGCCGGGGCAGAGAUGUGAGACCCUCAGGGGCAUCUUUGGGUGCCACCCACUCUCCCCUGGCAUUUAUCAAGCAACCAUGCACUCACACGUCGCCUCCUUUGACCGGAAGAGUGUUGAGUUUCCAGGCACUUGCGCUUCUGCUUUUACCAAGUCCUGUGGCUCCUCCAGCUCAUUGCGCCUUUUCAAGGUGGAAAUUGGGAAGGAGAAACAAGUCCAGCAGUCCCAUUGUGUUCAUUUCAAAGAUGUAGGUUCAUGGGACCCAGGUUUGUCUGCAGAGAGAGCCCCGACCUGAUGAGGUAAGCACUCAUUGGCAUCUAGAGACUCUUGAACCGAUUGAAGCUAAAAGAAAUACAUUGGCUCAAACUAAGUAAAAAUCAUGUGAUAGCCUAGUGAAAGUGUAGAGAUUCUGGGUCCACAGAAGUUCCCUAUAUACCACUUUGGCUGUUUUGGUUACAGAAAGCCUCAUAAAAGGUAACUCAAACCAGUCACAGACUGUGUUUUAUGAUUUUUAGACUAAUUACAUAACUGAAAAUUCCAGAGGGAGAUCAGGCAUGGUUUGAUCAGGGUGCUAACUCAGUUUUUCAGCAUUUCUCUUGGUCUGUGUUUCUCUAUAGCAUUAGCUUUGUCCUCAGGCUGGCUUUUCUUGUGAUGGCAAAAUAACUGCCAAUUUUCCAGUCAUUAAAUGUGUAUUCCCCAUUGUCCAAAACCCGAAUCUUUUCUUACCCCAAGUACUCAACAAAAAUUCCAAUGCUUCACUUUGAUUAAACCCCACUGAGCCAA